AGACGCUGUGAAGAGAGGAGCCGCGGCGGUCAGUACCUUCGAGGAAAUGAAGGAACCAGAUGAUCAGGAUACUGAUGGGGAGAAAUCAGUUACAUCAAAGAGUGAUGGGAAGAAGUCUCUGAGGUCUUCUAAAUCAGAAUCAAGAUCUCCUGUUCAAGAAGAUAACACAUUUUUAGAAGAUGACACAGAUGAAACAUUUACCAAAGGGGAAGGAUCAUAUUUAGAAGAAGACUCAGAUGAGGAACGUUUGGAAGGAAGUUUGAGUUCAUUUCAGUAUGGUGAUUUGCAAAGCACUACAGUACCUCAGCAAACCCCUGCUCCAGCUGUGGAAGAAGCAGAGGAGGAAGUUAAGAAGAAAAUAUCAGAGAGCUUCUUCUAUGAUUAUAUGGAGCUUGCUUCGAUGCCUUUUGUGACUCUGGAUUCAAACAUACCACUGGAUCUUCUCACACUUGUACAUUCUUUUGGUUAUGACUGUAGAAAGCGAGCCAACCUACAACUUCUGGACGACAGUAUCGCCAUAUACAUAGCUGGGAACCAACUGAUCUUUCUGAAUUUGAAAACCAAGGAACAGAUCUACCUGCGAAGUAGCAGUGGUGAAGGAAUUGGCGUCAUUGGGGUUCAUCCACAUAAAACUUAUUUCACAGUAGCUGAAAAAGGGAGUUUUCCAGAUAUUAUCAUCUAUGAAUAUCCUUCUCUGAGACCAUACAGAGUCCUUCGAGAUGGGACUGAGAAGGGAUAUGCUUAUGUGGACUUUAACUACAGCGGUAACUUGCUGGCCUCUGUUGGUAGUAACCCUGACUACACACUGACUAUCUGGAACUGGAAAGAAGAACAACCCAUACUAAGGACAAAAGCUUUUUCUCAGGAAGUUUUUAAGGUUACUUUCAAUCCUGAUAAGGAAGAGCAGCUUACUACAUCGGGAUCAGGCCACAUCAAGUUCUGGGAAAUGGCUUUUACGUUCACCGGUCUCAAGCUGCAGGGAUCACUAGGUCGAUUUGGCAAAACAAUCACUACUGAUAUAGAAGGCUACAUGGAGCUCCCAGAUGGGAAGGUGCUCUCAGGGUCAGAAUGGGGCAACAUGCUGCUUUGGGAAGGUGGUCUGAUCAAAGUGGAGCUCUGUCGAGGGACAAGCAAGUCAUGUCACAAUGGUCCCAUUAACCAGAUAAUGCUGUAUGAGGGUGAAGUUAUCACUGUUGGGUCAGAUGGAUAUGUUAGGAUAUGGGAUUUUGAGACAAUAGACACUGCUGAUGUAAUAGAUGAGACUGGAUUGUUGGAGAUUGAGCCUAUUAAUGAACUUCAAGUAGACAAGAAUGUGAAUCUCUUCUCUAUGAUAAAAAUGAAUGAAACUGGAAAUAACUUUUGGUUGGCUCAGGAUGCCAAUGGAGCCAUAUGGAAGCUUGACCUUAGUUUUUCAAAUAUUACCCAGGACCCAGAAUGCCUCUUCUCCUUCCAUUCUGGAGCUAUUGAAGCCGUGGCUGUUUCUCCUCUCACUUAUCUCAUGGCCACAACUGCCUUGGACUGCUCUGUUCGAAUCUAUGAUUUUGCUAGCAAAACUCCUUUGGCCCAGAUGAAAUUCAAACAAGGAGGUACUGCCCUUGUUUGGGUACCCCGAAUGGUAAACUUCACUGGAGCACAAAUUAUUGUAGGAUUUGAAGAUGGAGUUGUUCGAAUUCUUGAACUUUAUGAUCCAAAAGGGCUCACGAUUUUUGCGGGACGGAAGAAAAUUUUGGAUGCUGAUAUUCAGUUGAAACAGGUUUUCAAACCCCAUACUGCUUGUGUCACUGCUUUAGCUUAUGAACGUGAUGGGGAAAUUCUAGCCACAGGGAGUAAAGAUCAAACUGUUUUCUUCUUUGAAGUGGAAAGGGAUUAUAAGCCGAUUGGUUAUAUUAAUACUCCUGGACCUGUGUGUCAGUUAAUGUGGUCUCCCAUGUCUCAUCCUGAAAGUACUUUACUAAUUAUCUGUGAAAAUGGCUAUAUUCUUGAAGCUCCACUUCCAACCAUAAAGCAAGAAGAGGAUGAUCAUGAUGUAGUCUCCUAUGAAAUCAAAGACAUGUGCAUAAAAUGUUUCCAUUUUUCAAGUGUCAAAUCUAAGAUUCUGAGAUUAAUAGAAAUUGAAAAGAGGGAGAGACAAAGGGAGUUGAAGGAGAAAAUAAGGGAAGAAAGGAGGAACAAGCUAGCAGCAGAGAUGGGAGAAGAUGGAGAAAAAGAAUUUCAGGAGGAGGAAGAGGAGAAAGAGGAGGAGGAGGAGGAAGAAGAGCCAUUACCUGAAAUAUUUAUUCCGUCAACCCCCUCUCCCAUCCUCUGUGGAUUUUACUCAGAGCCAGGGAAGUUCUGGGUUUCUUUGGGUGGCUAUGAUUCUGGUUUUCUAUAUCACUGUGAGUUCCCCCCUUGUGAUGAAAGCAGUGAUUUCAAAGAACAAAAAGAUGAACCUAUUGAUGUCCGUUAUCUUGCGGAUACAGAGGACAAUCCCAUCCAAACUAUCACUUUCAACAUUAACAAAGUUAUGAUGUUUUGUGGAAUGAAAAAUGGAGCAAUUCGAGUCUAUGUCCUAAAUCAAAAUGAUCCUUCAUUGACCAGUUUGGUGGACUACUGGCACUUCAAUAUGCAUGACAAUAAUUAUGGAUGUAUUAAAAGUAUUGCUAAUAGCUUUGAUGAUCGUUUCUUGGUGACUGCUGGAGCAGAUGGCAAUAUCUUUGUUUUCAACAUUUUUUCUGAAUUUAUGCUAAGGAAAGACAUGAAGGCCAAAGUUCCAUCUCCCAGGUUUGGAAUUGAAACAGAGCCAAUUCCAGAAGACAUUGAAGAUCCCAAAGCCUACAGUAUCGAGAAUGCUAGGAGAAAAAGAGAACAUGACAAGUUAAUGAAAGAAGUGGGAGAAAUAAAGGCACGGAAGAGAGAGCAAAUCAAAGCUUUGAGGAGUGAAUUUUGUAAUCUAUUAGAAAUGAAUGAAAAAUUACCAAAGCAUAUGCAGUUUAAACGAACAGAUUUUGAUGUAGAUUCCCAAAUCCGUGCUGAGAUGCACAGAAAAACAGCUUUCAAAAUUCAACAAGUGGAAAAGGAAUUAGCUUGGGAAAAAGAGAAACAUGAACUCGGCCUAAUGAAGCUAAAGAAUCGAUUUCGAGAUCCACUGGAAAGUGAUACUAUUGUGGUUCAUGCCAUACUGAGUGACCACAAGAUAUCCUCUUACAGGCUGGUGCAGCCCUCUAAGUACUCCAAAUUCAAACGAGCUAGUCAAUCAGAGAGAAAACCAAGCAAAUUGGACAGGUUUGAAAAAGAGGGACCUGGAAGAAAGGACAGCCAGAGAGAUGCAGGUGGGAGUGUUACCAUACAAGAAGAAUCAAUAAUAGAAAAAGGGAAGAAAUUUCGGCCUAAAACCCUAAGUGAAAUCAUCGUGGAAAAUCAAAUUGAGAAAACGAGAAAACUUAUAUUAAAAGCUGAAAGGGCACAACUAAAGAUUCAACAGCGAAAAAAAGAAUGGGAGGAACUAUACAAGAGUAAACCUGGUGAUGACUAUGAAGAUCCCAAAGAUCUUCAAGCCAUCAAAGAAGCCCAGGUGUAUAUGGGAGAUUUCAAUCUGAAGACAGCCCCAGACUACAAGAUACCUGAGCACAUGAGAAUAAAUGCUGCCAAGAAGGAAGAGGAACUAGGACACCUAGAUUCUUUGGUCCAUGGAAAUAAAAGGCACAUGAACAAGUGCAUUCUCUCUCUUAGAGACCUUAAAGUGGCUGUUGUUGAGGAAAUACAGUGCCUGGUACAAGAACUGAAGAACAUUCAGUCGACUCUUCACAUAUCCAAGCACAUACCCAUUCCCAAAAUUCCUCAGAUACACCCAGAAGAAGUUCCAGAAAAGAGAUUUCAGUAUGAUGAAGAAACUCUCCUAAAUUUUAAGCAACAGCAAAUGAAAAGUAAAGAUGAAAAGUCCCCCGGAGUGGAACAGACAGGGUCUGGAGGCCCAGUUGGAGGAUUCCUCAAACUCUCUUCUAGAAAGGAUGGGGAUUUGACAACCCGUGAUUCAAUAUCUAGAUCAUCAAAGGCAUCAACAUUCAGCCUAGAUAUACCAAAGUGUUUGGAAUUUGAAAAAGCAGAGCCAACGGAUGUGGAGCUGGAAAUUAUGAAGAGAGACGAGAUUAAACACGUGUACAUGCAACAGUAUUUGGUCAACAGGAUCAAAGAACUGGUUGUCACUUUCGAUGCAGAACUCCGUCUCCUUAGACAUCAGAAACUAAAACUAGAUACUCAGAUGAAAUUAUCUGACCUGCACCAUGUCACCUUAUUUCAAGAAAUACUUCUCCUGAAGAAUUUUGAAAAACAGGAGAACAUACUUCAAGAACGUGUUAAUUCCUUAGACAAAGAGGAACAGUACAUGCAAUGGAAAAUAAAUGAAACUCUUAAAGAGAUGGAAGAGAAAAAGAAUGAAAUCACCAAACUCCAGGAGCAAGAAAAGGCACUCUAUGCUGGUUUUCAAGCAGCCAUUGGAGAAAACAAUAAAUUUGCAAACUUCCUCAUGAAGGUCCUAAAGAAGAAGAUUAAACGGGUAAAGAAAAAAGAAGUUGAAGGAGAUGCUGAUGAAGAUGAGGAGAGUGAGGAAUCAAGUGAAGAAGAAUCUAGCUUGGAGAGUGAUGAAGAUGAGUCUGAAUCAGAAGAUGAGGUUUUUGAUGAUUCUAUUUGCCCAACAAAUUGUGAUGUGGCUCUUUUUGAGCUGGCCCUUCACCUUCGAGAGAAAAGGCUGGACAUUGAGGAGGCUUUAGUUGAAGAAAAGAAAAUUGUUGAUAACCUCAAAAAGGAAUAUGAUACAUUGUCAAAAAAAGUGAAAAUUGUGGCAACUAAUCUGAAUGCAGCAGAGGAGGCCCUGGAGGCUUAUCAGCGAGAGAAGCAGCAGCGGCUGAAUGAACUGCUAGUUGUGAUUCCGCUCAAGCUCCACCAGAUAGAGUAUGUGGUAUUUGGAGAAAUACCUAGCGAUCUUUCUGGUACUUUGGUCUUCUCUAACCAUGCCUUGAGACGGCUGCAAGAACGAAUCCAUGAGCUCCAGGAGGAAAAUUCCAAGCAGCAAAAACUUAACAAAGAAUGGAGAGAGAGACGUAAACAGCUCAUCCGAGAAAAGAGAGAAAUGACAAAAACCAUACACAAAAUGGAGGAAACAGUCCGGCAGCUCAUGAUCAGCAAGUUUGGCCGUGUGGUAAAUCUAGAAGCCCUUCAAACGCUUUCUGUUAAUACAACACUUGAAGAACUGAAGAUCAGAAAACUUCGAAAGGAGCUAGCAAAUGCGAAAGAGAUGAAGAUGUGGGAGGAAAAGAUUGCUCAAAUGCGAUGGGAACUGAUGAUGAAGACAAAAGAACACACCAGAAAGCUUUAUCAGAUGAAUGAUUUGUGUAUUGAAAAGAAGAAACUUGAUUCUCGGUUGAAUACACUACAGAAUCAGCAGGGCAAUGCCUUCCAGGGCCCUCGGGAAGCAGAUGUUGUGGCAAGAGAGGAGGUCACUGAAUUGAUCCAACUCCAGGCGGAAAGGAUUUCGGCCUUAAAGGAGGAGAUUGCUCUUUUGCGUAGGAAAGGCAGUCUUAUCCUCCCACCCAUUCAGUCUCCACGAGAGAAAGAGAUACAGCCCGCAGACCUUUGAGUUUGCUAUUUUCUCAAACCCAUACAAGAUUUCUGACAUAACUCACUGGAAGUUCUGUCUCCUCAUCACCUCCAACAAUCUUAUUACUUUAAACUGAACUCGCCUGAAAGUGUAAAACCAGAUCCAGUCACGUUAAGUCACUUUAAGAAUCUCUCUACAAUUUGGUUAUCUUAGAACUGACUGCAGCACCCAACCUCUGUUAUGAAACUGAAUCAUUUUAGAUGUUUCGAACCUACUAGAUUGAAUAUGAAGUCUCGGAAGGCUGUGUUUCAUGAUUGCAGCAAAUCACCUGUAAUAUAUUUUGUUUUAGGAAAAUUUGAUUUGGGGGUAUCCUGAAUUUUUAGCCCUUGGCAAGAAAAACUAUCAUUCAGCAAUUCAUGAGAAAACUUUGUUUUCUUGAUCCUUAGAAAAUAAACUUAGAUGUUAUUAAGUGUUCUCUGAGAGGAUGCAGGAGAAAAGGACAUUUUGUCAGCUAUAUCUUAGAAUAGAAAUGCAAAUUUCAGUUUUGGCAUUGUUGACUUCAUAAAGCAGUGUUUUGAGGGCUCAGGAUUCAGGAAAUACAAACAGACAUGGCAGAGCAGUUUGCUUUGGGUUGGCAGAAAGCAGGAAAAUAACCAGCCUUCUUGGAUUGCCCACAGUUUUUGUAGACUCCUCAGUUCUGAGUGGAGCAGAGGGGCAUGCUUAAUAAAACAGUCAAUAAAGAGGCUUUUCUUUAAAGAUUUCUGCAACUCCGUCAGAAUUCUAAGUUUUCCCCAUAGUUUCUCAUGUCCCCUGCCAUUUUCUUUCAGGUUUUACUUGGGCCAUUUGCUGGUUUUGAUAUAGAUGAGGAGAUAAUGAAAUAGAUUUACUAGAGAUCAUCUUUAACAAUCACCUUUGAUUAUGCAUAACAUUUUAAACUAAUUGAAGAGUAUCCUUUUGGUUUGGGGGUAAGUGCUCAUUGAAGUUCAUGGCUAUAACCAUUGCAGGAUAAUCUCACUGACAUUUGGAAUCCUGUUAGUAACAGAGCAUAGCUCUUUAGAUUAAGAGCUCUGUAUUAACGAGCUACUCAUUGAGGCUGUUCCAGGAUAAGCUGGUCACUGAGAAGGGCGGGUGAAGAAAGGAACAUUGCAUAAAUGUAGAAGGGAACUCAGCAAUGCCAAGUCUUCCUCACCUGUGAUUAGCCUGCUAAUGUGCCCCCCAAAAUUACAGACAGGUCUUGCUUUCUUUGUACAUCAGCAUAUUCUUAGAGGUGGCCACUUGGCCUAUUGUCUUCCUAAGAUUCCUUCAUAUUCCUAUUUAAGAGGUCAGAAUACCUUAUUGUUUGCACUUGUCACCAUUAAUUUCUGAUGUAGUCACUUCUCUACUGGAGAGCACCCACUUUUUUUUUUAAAUCACUUUCUGUGUUGUAUAUCCUAAGCCAUGUGUGCCUUUCAAGUAUUUUUAAAAAUAUGCUAGUCAUAGCCCUGAGUGUCUUAUUUAUUGCGGUAAAAAAUUACCCCCAAACUUAGCUUGAAACAACAAACUUGUGAUCUCACCCAGGAGUGAGAGGGUUUCUGAGGUCCAGGAAUCUGGGGACAGCUUGGCCGGGUGUUCUGGCUCAGGGUCUUUCGUGGAGUUGCAGUCACACUAGGAGCUGGGGCUGCAGCCAUCUGAAGCUUGGCUGGAGCUGGAGGGGCUAUUAGCAAAUUCACUCCCUUGGCCAUUAGGCAGGGCUUCAGUUCCUCGCCAUGUGGGCCUCUCCAUAGGGCCGCUUGGGAUAUGACUUCUCCCAGAGCAAGUGAUCCAAGAGUGAGGGAGACAGCAAGAGAGAAUGAUGUAUACAAGAGCCACAGUCUUUUACAGCCCAAGCUCAGAAGUGACAUAGCGUCACUAUUGUCAUAUGGGUCACAGGCUGACCCUGUGUGAUGUGGGAGGGGACUGAACAGGGUGUGAAUGCCAGGUGGGGGUCACCGGGGCCUUCGUGGGAGCUGGCAGCCACAAGAAGCAGCUGCCUGGAGAGAGUGGCUGGUCUCUGAGAAAGGUCUUGAGGCGAUACCAUCCCCUUGGUAAUUGUAGAGAAUCAGGAGAAGUUACGUUAUCUUCCUGGGCCUCAUUUUAUUAUCUGACAAAUGAAGGAUUGGUAGAAUGGGUUCCUUCCCAUUCUGAGAUUCUGAUUCUGAUUGCAGCAAGAAUGGACCUACAGUCUACAGAAGAGCCACAUCAGGACUUGCUGUGCAUUUCAACUGAGAGGAAAGCUAAUCGGGAUAAUUAUUCCCAAACUGAGCUGGACUAAAUCACUAGUUAAUUCUACAAUAUUCAGGGCUUCAUUCCGCAUGUUUGGGAAUUGACGACAGUUAACACUGAAUUACUUUAUUUUGAAUUGGACAAAAUAUGUUGAUAGCUUUAGGUUCAUUUCAACUUGAUUCCAGGCUUAGUCUUAAAUCUGUAGUUAAGUUAGAGCAUCUGAGUCUUUGGGAAGUUAAGCUUCAAACACAAGUAGACCAGCAGGGUGUGGCAUGGGCAGGGUGGCUGGGAAGCUAUCCUGCUCCUGGCACACUUCCCUGCCUUCUGCUGUGCUCCCAGAGGAGCAGCCUCACCUCUGAGGGUAAGGCCAAAAAUCAGCCUACACUGAGUUACUUGUGGGUCAAUUGUUCAUAUAACUUGGCUCUUCUGAACUGUCAUCCAUAGUAUCACCGAUGAUCAAUCUCAGCAUUGGAAGAAAAAGAAACCACAGAGUCCAGCCCCUCUGUCACAACUUCAGAGUAAAGGAGUUGCUCAUGCCUGCCAGCCAGCCUGUCCCACCACAGCGGGCUCCCCAGCUUAGGGAGGUCUGUGAGCCAUGUGCUAAAUUUCUCUUUAGAGCUAAAUCCAUUGAGUGCUAUGAUUCCAGUGCUGUGCAGAAAGCAGAUGUUUCACCUAUCACUUCAGAAAAGUUCACCAGACUUCAUUUUGACAGCUACCUUAGAUCAUCAAGGAGAAAAAGGAAAAAAUGUAAAAACCAGUGGGGCUAGAAGGUGAGUUACAGCUCAGAUUGGGGGGCCUCUGGAUAGCAAAGCAAUGACUGAGAGCGUCAGCCCUACCCACCCCAGAAGUGAGCUCUGGGCCGUGAUGCCAGGUUGUCUGAAAUCACAGUAUCUUAUUUUUUCUCUUCUCUUCCCUGCUCUGCUUCUCAUUUCCUAACAUUUACCUGUUCCUUACAGUCCUUCCUUUUAAAUAAUAUUUUUAAAAUACUGCUUUCCUGAAAACCAUGCUGCACUUCCACAUGAAGUUCUCUCUGACGUUGAGCUUGAUGGAAAAAGGAUGCAGAAGUCAGGAAUAGCAGGUGCUAUACUUAUUUUGGCCAGCAGAGGAUGCACUUGCCCUAAACAGUCAGAGUGACUCUUCCCUAGGACCCUGUUUAUCAAAUUCUUCAUGUUUAAAAGCCAGGGUCUGGCCCCCCACUUAACGAGAUUGUCUCAAGUGGCAUUUCAUCUGUAACUCAAUUUUACAGAAAUCUAGAAAAUACAGGCUCCCCCCACCCUCUCCAGCCCCAAAACACAAAGCGUAGUAAGGCUUUCAUUGCAAGCAUCAGUCUCCAUCUAAUUCCACUUCCACAUAUAAAGAUUUUAAAAUUUCAAUUAAAAAAGAAUCUAUGGUUGAUCCUUUGGUUGGACAACAGUAAGUAAAUGUUGAUUUUAAACUAGUGAGUCAACUACUCUGGCAAUGUUGGUGUAUCUUUGGAAAGAAGGGAAGUGAAUUUAUUAUGCACCAUAUGUCCAUGUGUGGCACAGCACUUAGCUAAACAGUAUUUUGGAGAAAAUAUUUGGUCUUCAACACACACCUAUAUAAAAAAGAUUAGUUCUAUUUCUUCAAUAUGACCUAAACUUCAUCUCAAGUCCAGUUGGUAAGAGAACUAUGAACCUGUUUUUCCUGGUCUGUUGUACAACGGUUCCCUUGUGGACUAAACGGUAAUGUGUUCUGCAUGAAUCCAAGCACAACUGACAUUCACUGUUUUAAAAAACAAAAAAGAGAAACAUUUACUACCUUUUUCAGAUCUCAUUUCUGAUGGACCUGAAAAUAUUGUAAGUGGGUAUUUUCUUCAAAUACUCAGAGACUGAAUUCUAACAUGUAAAGAAAAUGCUGACUCACACAUGACUCAGUUUGAAGGUUACAGGGAAGACUAAACAUUUAUUUAGAAGUUACAGUGUUUGUUUUUACAGAGAUAUGUUGCCACGGAUUAUUGAUUCUGGAAGGUUUUUUAAUGCUCAUAGUGCUGUACACAUCUUGGUCUGUUCUCAUGGGCAUCUUAGGAAAAUGUUUCCCGUAGCACCGGAUCCAGCCAUCUGUGUGGGUGUCUCCAGGCUGUGAUACCGUGCCCCUUGCUGUUCCCUCAUGCUCGUGAUGAACCAUGUGCCUGGGAUCCUUCCUCUUGCCAGCUUAUCUGUGGGCCUCCUGCAGCCUCGCCUGCCACUGCAGAGGCCCCAGGUUAGGAGUCUGUCCCGCGCCAGCCUGUGCGGUGCUUUCCUGGGUGACUCCUGUUAGGUGGCAGCUUCUUUAUUUUCCCUCUCCAACCUCAACGGGUAGGACUCCUUAUGUCUCUCCAGAAUUAUAAAACAUAUACAUUUAUUUACAAGUGCAUAAAUAUAUAAAUAUGGCUAUAAUAGAAAAAUAAAUACCAAUUUUCUCUGUC